GCCGUGCUAGCCGUUGGGCCUGCCUCGGAGGAGGCGUCGCCGCCGCCGCUGCCGCUGCCGGCGCCGUUGCCGCUGCCGGGAAACACAAGGAAAGGGAACCAGCGCAGCGUGGCGAUGGGCGGGGGUAGAGCCCCGCCGGAGAGGCUGGGCGGCUGCCGGUGACAGACUGUGCCCUGUCCACGGUGCCUCCUGCAUGUCCUGCUGCCCUGAGCUGUCCCGAGCUAGGUGACAGCGUACCACGCUGCCACCAUGAAUGAGGUGUCUGUCAUCAAAGAAGGCUGGCUCCACAAGCGUGGUGAAUACAUCAAGACCUGGAGGCCACGGUACUUCCUGCUGAAGAGCGACGGCUCCUUCAUUGGGUACAAGGAGAGGCCCGAGGCCCCUGAUCAGACUCUACCCCCCUUAAACAACUUCUCCGUAGCAGAAUGCCAGCUGAUGAAGACCGAGAGGCCGCGACCCAACACCUUUGUCAUACGCUGCCUGCAGUGGACCACAGUCAUCGAGAGGACCUUCCACGUGGAUUCUCCAGACGAGAGGGAGGAGUGGAUGCGGGCCAUCCAGAUGGUCGCCAACAGCCUCAAGCAGCGGGCCCCAGGCGAGGACCCCAUGGACUACAAGUGUGGCUCCCCCAGUGACUCCUCCACGACUGAGGAGAUGGAAGUGGCGGUCAGCAAGGCACGGGCUAAAGUGACCAUGAAUGACUUCGACUAUCUCAAACUCCUUGGCAAGGGAACCUUUGGCAAAGUCAUCCUGGUGCGGGAGAAGGCCACUGGCCGCUACUACGCCAUGAAGAUCCUGCGGAAGGAAGUCAUCAUUGCCAAGGAUGAAGUCGCUCACACAGUCACCGAGAGCCGGGUCCUCCAGAACACCAGGCACCCGUUCCUCACUGCGCUGAAGUAUGCCUUCCAGACCCACGACCGCCUGUGCUUUGUGAUGGAGUAUGCCAACGGGGGUGAGCUGUUCUUCCACCUGUCCCGGGAGCGUGUCUUCACAGAGGAGCGGGCCCGGUUUUAUGGUGCAGAGAUUGUCUCGGCUCUUGAGUACUUGCACUCGCGGGACGUGGUAUACCGCGACAUCAAGCUGGAAAACCUCAUGCUGGACAAAGAUGGCCACAUCAAGAUCACUGACUUUGGCCUCUGCAAAGAGGGCAUCAGUGACGGGGCCACCAUGAAAACCUUCUGUGGGACCCCGGAGUACCUGGCGCCUGAGGUGCUGGAGGACAAUGACUAUGGCCGGGCCGUGGACUGGUGGGGGCUGGGUGUGGUCAUGUACGAGAUGAUGUGCGGCCGCCUGCCCUUCUACAACCAGGACCACGAGCGCCUCUUCGAGCUCAUCCUCAUGGAAGAGAUCCGCUUCCCGCGCACGCUCAGCCCCGAGGCCAAGUCCCUGCUUGCUGGGCUGCUUAAGAAGGACCCCAAGCAGAGGCUUGGUGGGGGGCCCAGCGAUGCCAAGGAGGUCAUGGAGCACAGGUUCUUCCUCAGCAUCAACUGGCAGGACGUGGUCCAGAAGAAGCUCCUGCCACCCUUCAAACCUCAGGUCACGUCCGAGGUCGACACAAGGUACUUCGAUGAUGAAUUUACCGCCCAGUCCAUCACAAUCACACCCCCUGACCGCUAUGACAGCCUGGGCUUACUGGAGCUGGACCAGCGGACCCACUUCCCCCAGUUCUCCUACUCGGCCAGCAUCCGCGAGUGAGCAGUCUGCCCACGCAGAGGACGCACGCUCGCUGCCAUCACCGCUGGGUGGUUUUUUCCCCCUAACUUUUUACUUAGCCUUUUUGGUUUGUGUCCCCACCCCCACCUCCUCACCCCCUUUCCAGUUCUUCUUCAGGCCCCUCCCAGACGCACCCCAGCGGCCCCUGCAGCCCCUGCCUCCAGCCUCCAGCCUCACCUUUGUGCCCAGACUCGCAUUUGGAAGACUCCACCUCCCGCCCAGGCCUGGGCUGUUGGGCGGUUGGAGAUUCAGGUUUUAAUCCACACAAGCCCCAGUGAGGGGUGAAGCAUGGCGCCUGGGGCCUGCCUGAGUUUCUGGCCUGGGUGUCGUGCUGGUGUCUGCCUCCGCGCUGCUGCAUCUGGACGAAGGCUGCCUUCUGGUGGGACGCGACACCCGGCAGACAGUGGUGCUGCCUUCCAGGCCCCGUGGCCUAGGCUCGGAGUGGCCAGGCACGGGGCGGUCCAAUCCCCCACCCGCUGUCCCCCUAUGGGGGCAGAAAAGCAAUAAUGUCCAGGGGCAGGCAGGGGCCCUUGGGAGCUGCAGGGCUGGGGGUUAGGGCUGCUCCCUGGUGAAUGGAGUCAGAUCCUAGGAUCUGUACCAUGGGGAACCAGGAGUGGCCGGGCUGGGUGCCGCCUCCUGGUCCGGCCUCCUCCCCACCAAACUGUCCUCACCCUAUGGAUGAGGCAGGAGGAACAUUUGGGGCCAAACCUGCCUGCCUCCCAGCCCCGUGCCUUACUAGGGCUUCCUUCCAGCUGGCCUUACCUCCCGCUGGACCCUGGGCCUGGCCUGGCCCCACUGGGGGCUAUGGGCUGGGCUCACCCUCUCCUCUGCGGGGGUGGAGGGCCACCAGCCUUGGCUGUUACAAUCUUACACCGGACAGUAUUGGGCCCCAUGGACUUGGUCAGGGAGGGGUGGGGGUGGGCAUCUCUGGUACCUAUUGGGGUGGGGGGCCUCUGAAAAGGGAGGCUCCUAGGCCCCCCUCACCCCUCCCUCUCCCCAGGGCCCCACGUUCUGCAGCCUUAAGGUUGAACAUGAGUGCACGUCCAUGUCAGUGCUGUGGGACUCCUGUGCGUGCCUCGGACUGCGUGUGUCGGCGGGACGCAGGCACACGUGGGUGUGUGUGCAUGUGUGUUUGUGUGAGGGCAGCGUGUCCUCCAGUGUGCAUGGUGUGUGGGCUUGGGCCCCAUCCCUGGCCCGAGCAUUUCAUCCUGUGGGGGAGGGGUGCUGACCUAGUGGGAGGAGCCCCACUGUGAUCCAUGAGCUGCCCUGCCCACGCCUCCCCUCCCUGUAGCAACACCUCUGGGUGUUUGGAGUUUAGCUUUUGUGGGUUUGCUCUCCCUAUCCCAUCUCCUGUACUACACAGUUCAUGGCAGGGUGGGGAGGGGUGGGGUUGGUUCGGGUGGGUGAGGGUCUUUUUCCUCUGUGUGCGAUGUUGUUAUCUGACAGUUCUCCGUCCCUACUGGCCUUUCUCCUCGUCUUCAUAUUUGUACGGUACAAGCAAUAAAGACACUCAUUUCAGACCAGGGCCCAGCCUGCACUCACGCCAGCCCAACCACUCUGGGCUUUGCCUUGGUGAUGGAGUCAGACCCCUGGGCCCCAGCUCCUCCUGUACUAGCCGUUCCCUUCAGCAAGGAGGGCACUGAGCUCAGGGUGAGGGCAGCUGGGGUGUGUGCAGGAGCUCAGGCUGGAGAGGGUGGGUGGAGCUGGUGCUGUGGGGCUGAGGGGUAUGGGAAGGCUCCCCGCAUGUGGGGGUGGGGUGGACAGAGACCACUCCAGGCCCUCAGUGCUGCUUAGGCUAAGAGAGGUGGGGUGGAGGGACAGGGCUGGAAGAUCUGGGUAGCCCAGAAUGAGGAGGGUGCCUGUGCUGUCACUGAAUGAGAGGGAGUGGUUCAUUCCACCCGGCUGCCGAGCCUCAGAGGGGGGCAUUCCUAUCCUGCCCCACCUCCCUGUUUAUGCUGCCACCUGGAAGCCUUGAGGCCCCCAAAUUCCAGUACAGACCCAGUGGUGUGUUCAUGGUGGCGUGGUUGCUGUCACCUGGGAGCUCCUGAGCGUUUGGUUAGAACCCUGUUCAGCUUGGGGUCAGCCCUCCCCUAGUCACUGCCCUUUAGCCUGGAUGUGUCUGGGCCCCUGCACUUCCCGUGCUUGAGUCACGUGGCUGCAUGGCCGGGCGCUGGCCGGAUGGAACACCUCCCCCAGCAAGGGACCAGGGACCAGAGCCCUGGCCUGCCCUGCUGAGCCCUGCUGUGCAGAGGGCCUGGCACAGAUGAAUUUGAGAUUUUGCCGCAAGGUGUUAGCACUUCACACCCAUUGAGUCUUUGAGAUUUUAAGUGAAUGUAAGCAGAAAAAGUCAGAUCCAAUUUACAGAAAUCAGAGUUAGCUACAGCUAGGACUCGUUUGGUUGGGGUUUUUUAGUUUGUCUUUCUAAAGUCAUGUGGACCUUAAUUUAAUUACAAAAGUCUACCCUGGUGGUCAUAAAAUAGGCAGGCCUAUGAAGAAAGGCCUUUUACUCUUCCAUCUCGUCCCAGCCCCGAGUUGACCCACGUUGCUGCUCCUCACACCAUGGUGAUGCAGGUCUCGUAGUGUGGGCACAGGCCUGGCUACCUCAUCUUUUUAGUGCCUCUCUCCUCUUCCACAGGAUGGGGUCCCACAGCUGCAGCAGCUGGCCCCGUAGUUGAGCAUGUGUGGUUAUCCUGUAGAGCUUUUCCCAAGAAGGGUGUUUGAACUUAGAGUCUUAAUAAAAUCUUACCAAAUAAAUUUUGAGUAGAAUAAUCGUCUUUUGCAAUGUACAUUUUAAAAAUUUCACACAUUCUUUUUUGUAUAUAAAGAACAGUGACUGGGCACAGUGGCUCAUGCCUGUAAUCCCAGCAAUUUGGGAGGCCGAGGCGGGCGGGUCUCUUGAGGCCAGGGGUUCGAGACCAGCCUGGGCAUCAUAGGGAGACCUUCAUCUCUACAAAAAAUACAAAAAUUAGCUGGGCAUGGUGGUGCAUGCCUGCAAUCCCAGCUAACUUGGAAGGCUGAGGUGAGGUGGGAAGAUCACUUGAGCCCAGGAGUUUGAGGCUGCAGUGAGCUAUGAUUGCGGCACUGCACUGCAGCCUGGGACAAUGAGACUGUGUCUCUAAAAAUAAAAAAAAAAAAAACAUGAUACAUGCUAUUAAAAAAGACAGCAAAGCAGGAGUAUAAGAAAGGAAAUUCACCCGAGGUCGCAGGGCCUUGAGUACUCAUUUUGGUGCUGAUUACCUCUCUGCAAAUGGACACGGCAUCAUAAAUUGGUAGUUUCCUGCUCUUUUUGUGUAAUCUUUUCCAGUUAAUGUGAAGCCUCUGGGGGCUGCCCUCGUGCACUGAUGGUUGUGUGGAGUCGGGGGCGGCAGUGCGAUUCCCUUUUAGCUGCUGCAUGGGGGGAACUCAGGCUUUCCAGCUGCUUCCUGGGGUUCCAUGGGGUAGACCCCUCAACCGCUUCAGCUGCCCCGUUAACAGGAAUUGACUUGGUUUCGUUUGGUGCUACCAGCAGUCCUGUAAUAAACUAGCUAUCCAUCUGUA